AGUCGCUGCACAGUCUGUCUCUUCGCCGGUUCCCGGCCCCGUGGAUCCUACUUCUCUGUCGCCCGCGGUUCGCCGCCCCGCUCGCCGCCGCGAUGCCAGUGUUUCAUACGCGCACGAUCGAGAGCAUCCUGGAGCCGGUGGCACAGCAGAUCUCCCACCUGGUGAUAAUGCACGAGGAGGGCGAGGUGGACGGCAAAGCCAUUCCUGACCUCACCGCGCCCGUGGCCGCCGUGCAGGCGGCCGUCAGCAACCUCGUCCGGGUUGGAAAAGAGACUGUUCAAACCACUGAGGAUCAGAUUUUGAAGAGAGAUAUGCCACCAGCAUUUAUUAAGGUUGAGAAUGCUUGCACCAAGCUUGUCCAGGCAGCUCAGAUGCUUCAGUCAGACCCUUACUCAGUGCCUGCUCGAGAUUAUCUAAUUGAUGGGUCAAGGGGCAUCCUCUCUGGAACAUCAGACCUGCUCCUUACCUUCGAUGAGGCUGAGGUCCGUAAAAUUAUUAGAGUUUGCAAAGGAAUUUUGGAAUAUCUUACAGUGGCAGAGGUGGUGGAGACUAUGGAAGAUUUGGUCACUUACACAAAGAAUCUUGGGCCAGGAAUGACUAAGAUGGCCAAGAUGAUUGACGAGAGACAGCAGGAGCUCACUCACCAGGAGCACCGAGUGAUGUUGGUGAACUCGAUGAACACCGUGAAAGAGUUGCUGCCAGUUCUCAUUUCAGCUAUGAAGAUUUUUGUAACAACUAAAAACUCAAAAAACCAAGGCAUAGAGGAAGCUUUAAAAAAUCGCAAUUUUACUGUAGAAAAAAUGAGUGCUGAAAUUAAUGAGAUAAUUCGUGUGUUACAACUCACCUCUUGGGAUGAAGAUGCCUGGGCCAGCAAGGACACUGAAGCCAUGAAGAGAGCAUUGGCCUCCAUAGACUCCAAACUGAACCAGGCCAAAGGUUGGCUCCGUGACCCUAGUGCCUCCCCAGGGGAUGCUGGUGAGCAGGCCAUCAGACAGAUCUUAGAUGAAGCUGGAAAAGUUGGUGAACUCUGUGCAGGCAAAGAACGCAGGGAGAUUCUGGGAACUUGCAAAAUGCUAGGGCAGAUGACUGAUCAAGUGGCUGACCUCCGUGCCAGAGGACAAGGAUCCUCACCGGUGGCCAUGCAGAAAGCUCAGCAGGUAUCUCAGGGUCUGGAUGUGCUCACAGCAAAAGUGGAAAAUGCAGCUCGCAAGCUGGAAGCCAUGACCAACUCAAAGCAGAGCAUUGCAAAGAAGAUCGAUGCUGCUCAGAACUGGCUUGCAGAUCCAAAUGGUGGACCGGAAGGAGAAGAGCAGAUUCGAGGUGCUUUGGCUGAAGCUCGGAAAAUAGCAGAAUUAUGUGAUGAUCCUAAAGAAAGAGAUGACAUUCUACGUUCCCUUGGGGAAAUAUCUGCUCUGACUUCUAAAUUAGCAGAUCUACGAAGACAGGGGAAAGGAGAUUCUCCAGAGGCUCGAGCCUUGGCCAAACAGGUGGCCACGGCCCUGCAGAACCUGCAGACCAAAACCAACCGGGCUGUGGCCAACAGCAGACCGGCCAAAGCAGCUGUACACCUUGAGGGCAAGAUUGAGCAAGCACAGCGGUGGAUUGAUAAUCCCACAGUGGAUGACCGUGGAGUCGGUCAGGCUGCCAUCCGGGGGCUUGUGGCCGAAGGGCAUCGUCUGGCUAAUGUUAUGAUGGGGCCUUAUCGGCAAGAUCUUCUCGCCAAGUGUGACCGAGUGGACCAGCUGACAGCCCAGCUGGCUGACCUGGCUGCCAGAGGGGAAGGGGAGAGUCCUCAGGCACGAGCACUUGCAUCUCAGCUCCAAGACUCCUUAAAGGAUCUAAAAGCUCGGAUGCAGGAGGCCAUGACUCAGGAAGUGUCAGAUGUUUUCAGCGAUACCACAACUCCCAUCAAGCUGUUGGCAGUGGCAGCCACGGCGCCUCCUGAUGCGCCUAACAGGGAAGAGGUAUUUGAUGAGAGGGCAGCUAACUUUGAAAACCAUUCAGGAAAGCUUGGUGCUACGGCCGAGAAGGCGGCUGCGGUUGGUACUGCUAAUAAAUCAACAGUGGAAGGCAUUCAGGCCUCAGUGAAGACGGCCCGAGAACUCACACCCCAGGUGGUCUCGGCUGCUCGUAUCUUACUUAGGAACCCUGGAAAUCAAGCUGCUUAUGAACAUUUUGAGACCAUGAAGAACCAGUGGAUCGAUAAUGUUGAAAAAAUGACAGGGCUGGUGGACGAAGCCAUUGAUACCAAAUCUCUGUUGGAUGCUUCAGAAGAAGCAAUUAAAAAAGACCUGGACAAGUGCAAGGUAGCUAUGGCCAACAUUCAGCCUCAGAUGCUGGUUGCUGGGGCAACCAGUAUUGCUCGUCGGGCCAACCGGAUCCUGCUGGUGGCUAAGAGGGAGGUGGAGAAUUCCGAGGAUCCCAAGUUCCGUGAGGCUGUGAAAGCUGCCUCUGAUGAAUUGAGCAAAACCAUCUCCCCGAUGGUGAUGGAUGCAAAAGCUGUGGCUGGAAACAUUUCCGACCCUGGACUGCAAAAGAGCUUCCUGGACUCAGGAUAUCGGAUCCUGGGAGCUGUGGCCAAGGUCAGAGAAGCCUUCCAACCUCAGGAGCCUGACUUCCCGCCGCCUCCACCAGACCUUGAACAACUCCGACUAACAGAUGAGCUUGCUCCUCCCAAACCACCUCUGCCUGAAGGUGAGGUCCCUCCACCUAGGCCUCCACCACCAGAGGAAAAGGAUGAAGAGUUCCCUGAGCAGAAGGCCGGGGAGGUGAUUAACCAGCCAAUGAUGAUGGCUGCCAGACAGCUCCAUGAUGAAGCUCGCAAAUGGUCCAGCAAGGGCAAUGACAUCAUUGCAGCAGCCAAGCGCAUGGCUCUGCUGAUGGCUGAGAUGUCUCGGCUGGUAAGAGGGGGCAGUGGUACCAAGCGGGCACUCAUUCAGUGUGCCAAGGACAUCGCCAAGGCCUCAGAUGAGGUGACUCGGUUGGCCAAGGAGGUUGCCAAGCAGUGCACAGAUAAACGGAUUAGAACCAACCUCUUACAGGUAUGUGAGCGAAUCCCAACCAUAAGCACCCAGCUCAAAAUCCUGUCCACAGUGAAGGCCACCAUGCUGGGCCGGACCAACAUCAGUGAUGAGGAGUCUGAGCAGGCCACAGAGAUGCUGGUUCACAAUGCCCAGAACCUCAUGCAGUCUGUGAAGGAGACUGUGCGGGAAGCUGAAGCUGCUUCAAUCAAAAUUCGAACAGAUGCUGGAUUUACACUGCGCUGGGUUAGAAAGACUCCCUGGUACCAGUAGGCACCUGGCUGAGCCUGGCUGGCACAGAAACCUCUACUAAAAAGAAGGAAAAUGAUCUGAGUCCCAGGAGCUGCCCAGAGUUGCUGGGAGCUGAAAAAUCACAUCCUGGCCUGGCACAUCAGAAAGGAAUGGGGGCCUCUUCAAAUUAGAAGACAUUUAUACUCUUUUUUCAUGGACACUUUGAAAUGUGUUUCUGUAUAAAGCCUGUAUUCUCAAACACAGUUACACUUGUGCACCCUCUAUCCCAAUAGGCAGACUGGGUUUCUAGCCCAUGGACUUCACAUAAGCUCAGAAUCCAAGUGAACACUAGCCAGACACUCUGCUCUGCCCUUGUUCCCUAGGGGACACUUCCCUCUGUUUCUCUUUCCUUGGCUCCCAUUCACUCUUCCAGAAUCCCAAGACCCAGGGCCCAGGCAAAUCAGUUACUAAGAAGAAAAUUGCUGUGCCUCCCAAAAUUGUUUUGAGCUUUCCAUGUUGCUGCCAACCAUACCUUCCUUCCCUGGGCUGUGCUACCUGGGUCCUUUUCAGAAGUGAGCUUUGCUGCUACAGGGGAAGGUGGCCUCUGUGGAGCCCCAGCAUAUGGGGGCCUGGAUUCAUUUCCUGCCCUUCCUCAGUUUAAUCCUUCUAGUUUCCCACAAUAUAAAACUGUACUUCACUGUCAGGAAGAAAUCACAGAAUCAUAUGAUUCUGCUUUUACCAUGCCCCUGAGCAAUGUCUGUGCUAGGGAAACUUCCCGUCCCAUAUCCUGCCUCAGCCCGCCAAGGUAGCCAUCCCAUGAACACACUGUGUCCUGGUGCUCUCUGCCACUGGAAGGGCAGAGUAGCCAGGGUGUGGCCCUGCCAUCUUCCCAGCAGGGCCACUCCCGGCACUCCAUGCUUAGUCACUGCCUGCAGAGGUCUGUGCUGAGGCCUUAUCAUUCAUUCUUAGCUCUUAAUUGUUCAUUUUGAGCUGAAAUGCUGCAUUUUAAUUUUAACCAAAACAUGUCUCCUAUCCUGGUUUUUGUAGCCUUCCUCCACAUCCUUUCUAAACAAGAUUUUAAAGACAUGUAGGUGUUUGUUCAUCUGUAACUCUAAAAGAUCCUUUUUAAAUUCAGUCCUAAGAAAGAGGAGUGCUUGUCCCCUAAGAGUGUUUAAUGGCAAGGCAGCCCUGUCUGAAGGACACUUCCUGCCUAAGGGAGAGUGGUAUUUGCAGACUAGAAUUCUAGUGCUGCUGAAGAUGAAUCAAUGGGAAAUACUACUCCUGUAAUUCCUACCUCCCUGCAACCAACUACAACCAAGCUCUCUGCAUCUACUCCCAAGUAUGGGGUUCAAGAGAGUAAUGGGUUUCAUAUUUCUUAUCACCACAGUAAGUUCCUACUAGGCAAAAUGAGAGGGCAGUGUUUCCUUUUUGGUACUUAUUACUGCUAAGUAUUUCCCAGCACAUGAAACCUUAUUUUUUCCCAAAGCCAGAACCAGAUGAGUAAAGGAGUAAGAACCUUGCCUGAACAUCCUUCCUUCCCACCCAUCGCUGUGUGUUAGUUCCCAACAUCGAAUGUGUACAACUUAAGUUGGUCCUUUACACUCAGGCUUUCACUAUUUCCUUUAUAAUGAGGAUGAUUAUUUUCAAGGCCCUCAGCAUAUUUGUAUAGUUGCUUGCCUGAUAUAAAUGCAAUAUUAAUGCCUUUAAAGUAUGAAUCUAUGCCAAAGAUCACUUGUUGUUUUACUAAAGAAAGAUUACUUAGAGGAAAUAAGAAAAAUCAUGUUUGCUCUCCCGGUUCUUCCAGUGGUUUGAGACACUGGUUUACACUUUAUGCCGGAUGUGCUUUUCUCCAAUAUCAGUGCUCGAGACACAGUGAAGCAAAUUAAAAAAAAAAAAAAAAAAAAUCCCUGAAUGAUGAUUAGAGACAUCACCGCUAAAAAACUACAUUUAUAAGCUAGGAUUUGUUAUAUGCAAAUAUUUUCUGCCUCUUCUUUUGUUCUGUUUAAAACAAUAAAAUGCAUUUGUAUAAAAAAUGCUUUAAAUGAUGGAUAUGUUACUUUAGCAAGAACUUUUAGGUCAGGUUUCUCCUUUGUUUUGAUGAAUAGUCAAUGAAACUAAUCCUCAAGAUCUGGAAACUAAAGAUUUUUAUUUAAUCCAAAUGUUGCACUGGAAGAAGAAAUCAACAGUGGUAUAUUUACUUAACAAGGAUGUGUGUAAUACAAGACAACCCUGGGGAUUACACACUUGAAGGAAUGGAAGUGGCAAAGGUUAACAGGCAGAAAGCAGCUGGAUGAAACAGUUUAUUUUCAUCUUAGAAGAUUCUAGCUAUCUGUGGAGACCACCACUGUUCCCCGAAAAGCUAAAGUUGUUAAGUUUGUAGGAGUACCACAGGUCCUUCCCCCUGCUGCAAGACAGAGACUUGCUCUGUUGCCCAGGCUGCAGUGCAGUGGUGCAAUCUCAGCUCACUGCAACCUCUGCCUCCCGGGUUCAAGCAAUUCUCCUGCCUCAGCCUCCCAUGUAGCUGGGAUUACAGGUGUGCGCCACCAUGCCUGGCUAAUUUUUGUAUUUUUAGUAGAGAUGGAGUUUCACCAUGUUGGCCAGGCUGGUCUCGAACUCCUGACCUCAAGUGAUCCGCCCACCUUGACCUCCCAAAGUGCUGGGAUUACAGGUGUGAUCCACCACGCCCGGCCACACAGGUCCAUUUUUCAUAUUCCAAAGCCCAGUAUAGAAUAAAUAGGGUUUUCAGGGAUCCACCAGGGCUAUAAAACAGAGUUAGCUUUUGGGGACAUAGUCCUCUUCUUCCUUAAAGAAACACUGACUAAAAUAGUAGGAGCAGGUUUUUAGAGUAGAGUUGGGACAUCACUUUUUCCCUGAUUUUCUAGAUCUGAAAGGGGUAACAUGUCAUUAAAGGGUGAUGAUAUUGAUAUUUAGUGUUGCCAACUGCUAUUAUCACUGCUUUAUCUUGGAAAGUUGCCGACUAUAAAGACAGAUUCCAGCCUGCUUGAGUUAAGGGAAAGGCCAAGGCUGCUACUGAAUUAGCAGUUUCUAAAACUGUCUUGUUUUUGCCAUUUACCAUAUGUUCACUGGUGCUGCCUUCCUGCUGUAGUAUAAUCAUUUUCUCAAAUCAGUUGCCUCUCAGGACAAGAUCAGCAUUUUCCUAGGGUCCUUCUGUAGCACCACUUAAGGAAUGAACCUAUCACAGGAACUCCCUUUGAAUAAAAUGAUGGUGACUCCCA